UUAGGUUUCCUUCUUCUUAGGAAUUCCACCAAAAUUACACGAGUAACACUAUACUAAAUUUUUACCUACUAUCAUUAAAAAAUAAUGACUUACUCAAAGCUCUGACACUCAUUAGAGCAGGUUGAUAUGGUAGAAAAUUCUAGCCCUAUGCAACUGGAGUGAUCUUGAUGCUAAGACAAUAUGACCCAAAACCUUGUCCUUUCCUUUUGGCUAUAUGAAUAUUUUCUAACUUUUGUGAACAAAAUAUGUCUCAUUUUCCUCAUGAUGGUGUUUCAAAAUGAAUUGAUGGGUGUUUUUCAGUUAUUAGUGGAUAGGAGCUCUCUUAGCUCAGCCCUUCAAAAACUUGUGUUUGAUGUUGUAAUUUUGUAAAUUAUCUCAAUGUAUGCCUAUAUGCUUACACACAUAAUCCCCUACCUAAAAGAUCAACCUUAGCUUAGAAUUUCUUCCUUUUUAUUUUUUUCCUCUAUUUUUUUUUUUUUUUUUUUUUUUUUGAGACAGGGUCUUGUUCUGUUGCUCAGGUUGGGGUGUAGGAGUACAAUCAUAGCUCACUGCAGCUUUUGAGCUCCUGGGCUCAGGCGAUCUUCCCACCUCACACUUCAGCCUCCCCUGAGAGCACAGGCAUGUACCACCACACCCAGUUGAUUUAAAAUCUAUUUUUUUGUACAGAUGCAGUUCCUAUGUUAUUCAGGCUGGUCUCGAACUUCUGGCCUCUAGUAGUCCUCCUGCUUCAACCUCCUCAGAGUACAGGCAUGAACCAUCAUUCCUGGCCCCUUACUAUUUCUAUAUUUUACUUUUAGUAUAAGUCUGUGAAAGAAGUAUAUUUCUCAUAGUUUGUUGAACUGCGCAGAUGAUGAUGUUGAAGGAUCUGCACGAUGGUUAUGAUGGUUGCUGUCAUUGCACUACAGUGCUUUUUAAAAAACUGAAAAUAUUCAUUUCUCACUAGAAUAGUCAUACAGGCAUUUAUUUGUUGCUUUAGAAUUUGGAAACUUCUUUUUAUAUUCAUAGUUGUAUUUCAUUCUGCCAGCAGAUUAGGCAGAUUCAUCCUCUCCCACUUUCCAGUGGUAGAAACAGGUGUCCUGAGGCAGUGAAGUAGUUGUUGGAAAAUCACUGUGGUUUGCUUUCCAGGGAUUUUCUUGUCCUCUGAGUGCGAAAGUAUCAUAAUACAUGGCACAUUCCCACAGGAAGUUUAGGGUGUGAAAAGUCAAUGUAUUAAUAUACAUAUGGGAUCCACUUCCACUCAAAGCAAAACACAUUGAGUCAAGUAUCAGAGCUCAGUGGGUGUACAUGAUGGCAUUUAAUUUUCCUAAAUUACUUCAUAUAAUUAAUAUACACUAAGCCUUUGUUAUGAUGCUACACAUCAUUUUUGGAGUCACAAGCUUUCAACCUUCAUCUAACUAAAAGAUGGAUAUCUUCAUUUUAUAUUAGGUGGUCUGGAAGCCAUAGUAGUGUUAAAGAGCACAUAGGGAAUGUUUUAGUCCAUUCGGAUUGCUGUAAGGAAAUACAAUAGACUGUGUGGCUUAUAAAUAACAGACAUUUAUUGCUGAGUUCUGGAGGCUGGGAAUUCAAGAUCAAGGUGUGGCAGAUUCAGUGUCUGGUGAGGACACACAUCUUUGUUUGUUGAUAGUGCCUUUUCCUUGUAUCCUCAUGUGGUGGAAGGGAUAAGGGAGUUCUCUGAGUUCCCUUUUGUAAGGGCACCAGUCCCAUUCAUAAGGCUCCAACCUCAUGACUUCAUCACCUCCCAAGGGCCUCACCUCCUGAUACUAUCAUCUUGGGGGUCAUGAUUUCAACAUAGGAAUUUGGAGUGACACAACCAUUCAGAUCAUAGCAGAGAGAGUGAGAUGAGACUUGCCGAACUCCAUAAAGCCAUAUGAAUAUUUUCAGUUCCAGUCCUAUUUCCAUUUUCAAAUGUUGAGUUAUGAACUUGAUUGAUGCCUCCUGGUAUUUUUCAAAAUGUUCUAGAGCUCUCAUGAUCAAUAUUAAACCUUUCCCAUUCAAAGGACAUGAUUAUUUUAUGUGAGUAAUGUGUUGCUAUUUGACAAAGGAGUACAACUAUAAAUAAAUCUUGACUAUCUUGAUGUAGGAAAUAAAUACACCUGUCAAGAUAUACUAUAAUGCUUUUGUAGUCAAAACAAUGAUGGGGCUAGCAUUGUGACUCAUGCUUGUAAUCCCAGCACUUUGGGAGGCCGAGGGAGGUGGAUGACUUGAGGUCAGGAGUUCGAGACUAGCCUGUCCUACAUGGUUAAACCGCAUCUCUACUAAAAAUACAAAAAUCAGCCAGGCAUGAUGGUGCAUGCCUGUAAUCCCUGAUACUCUGGAGGCUGAGGAAAGAGAAUCACUUCACUCCAGGAUGCAGGGGUUACAGUGAGCCAAGACGGUGUCACUGCACUCUAGCUAGGCACCAGAGUGAGACUCGAUCUCAAAAACAAACAAAGAAAAAAUGGUGGAUAGAAUAGGAUAUUAUUUAAAUGAAAACUGUAAGGGGAGUUGUAUGCUCUCAAAUGUCAUUAUGCACAGUCUAAUAUGUCCCUUUCACUCUGCCACUCUACCUGCUAAUUUGCUUCCUUAAUUCAGACUUACCUAUUAGGUUAUUAGUUAUAAUAUAGGUUGACAAUUAUGCAGCUUUUCUUCUUUACCAAGACCUGUUCCAAGUGCUUUUUAUAUUAACUCAUUGGUGUCAACCACUCUACCCCAUAGUAACCAUUAGUAUUAGUUUCCUAUCUGUGCUGUGGUAACAAGUUACUACAGACCUAGUGGCUUCAUACAGUUCUACCACUCAGAAGUCCAAAAUGAGACUUAGGAGGCUAAAAUCAAGGUAUCAUCAGGACUUCAUUAUUUUUGGAAGCUCUGCGAGAGGAUACAUCUCCCUACCUUUUCAAGAUUCUAGAAACUUCCUACUUUCGUUGGCUCAUAGGCUCCUUUCUCCACCUUCAAUGCCAGUAGACUGAGUCCUUGUUCUGUCAUCUUUUUGUUUGUCCCUCUUUUUCCCUUUUCUAUGGGCACAGUGGAUAACCUGGAAUGAUCUCCCAAUUUCAAGGUCUGCUGACUGGGAAUCUUAAUUCCACCUGCCUCUUUCAUUCAAAUCCCUUUUCCAUGUAAGACCACACAACCGCGCAUAUUAACACAUGGGCAUCUCAGGGGGACCAUUAUUAUGCAGACCACACAGUUGUUAUCUUCAUUUUAUAGCCAAGAAAGACAAACAGAGUUAAAUCACUUACUCAGAUUGUUGGUCUGCUAAAUGGUAGAGCUAGUUAAAAUUAGGAGCAUACGCAGGGAAGCUAGGCAGUGUUGUGAUCAAGGCCCUUGGCCCCCUAAAGUUUCAAUGAAAAAUCAUGGAGAUAAUCAGUGACUAUUACUGUCCACUCAACCGGGUUGCACAGAGGGAGAGAGAGACCAGGAGCCUGGCUGGCUGAUGAUAAUGUCUUACCCUAUUGCUAGCAGUGUUGGUUCCUGGGUUCUCUGCACUGUGGCUUUCAAAAGAACAGAGCAGCUUUGGUGACCCCACUUGUUGUGCCAUAACUGUAGAGGCCAAGGCUUUUUAUCCCCUAAAGUUUUACUGAAAAAUUACUGACUAGGCAGACCAAUUUACAGGUGAAAUGACAUACAAACAUGCUUAAUGCAGAUACAAAGGAGCCUUCAGAAUGAAGACGCAACCUCCCUGUGAGAUCCUGAAGCUUAUAUACCAACCUGAGUUUACAGAAAGAGUGGGGGCUUGGAUCCCAGUAAUACAGAUGAUGGGAGGGGGAGAAGAGGAAUUCUGUCGAGGAGAUUACUAGAACGGAGAUUAACUUGUAAAUAACUCUUUUUGAAAAUUAAAUAAUCCUUGAGGACAACCUUGGAAAACUGUCUGUUGAGGUGUGGUGUCAUCUUGGUUUUUUUCUGCAGUCGAUAAGGAUAUAACAGGAAGGGGUUAAAAACAAUUAUUAUCCUUGUGGGAGUCUGUGUCUUAGGCAAAUAAAGAAACUUCAGCUACUUUGGGAGAGGUAGUGGGAGAGGGGGAGGUUGGACUUCUUCAACUCAGCCUGUCAAAAUGCCAUAUUUUGGGGUAUUGUUUUCUGAGCCUCAGCAGGACUCAUACAGUAUUGUGGGAUUUGGGGCUGAGCCAUGGUGGGACAGAUUUUCCCCUGAGAUCCUUAUGCAUCCAAAUCAGUAGGUGCCUGUUCACGUUCAACAUGAAAAAACUGACACAAAGCAAUGAGUAGGAAAUUGGGGGGUAAAUGUAAUGAAACAAACGUGUGUUAAACAACAUUUCUCCAUAAUAUUAAACUAAUGUGAAGAAUUUAGAGUCAGGAAUUUUUCUGGAAAGUGUAGGCUCCAACUUCCUCAGAGUAUGAUUUGUAGGAUGCUCUUCCCCAUUCACUACUCCACCCAACAUUUCUGACAGUUAUCAGAAGAAAGAGACCUGGUAUAAUUAAUCAAACUCAAGACAUUUAGGUCAUUGUUUGCUUGAGAUUCAUCAGGAGGUCUUCUAACCAUGCUGCAAACACUUUAACUCAUCAGGGCUUCACAGAUGAAUUUACUGAUUCCACAAACUUGUAAAUUGUAUUUCCAGAGCCAAUGUGAACUCUCUCAGUUAUGGUUUUUGUCUUGAAGACUGUGACUUUCAUUUAAAAUGUUGUUUCAAUGAUGCAUUUUCUGAACUCAAUGAAAUUAUGAAGGGACAGAUUUUAAAGUCCAUAACGAUUUUGUUUUAUUAAAGCUGCCAAAUAUUUUUAAUAUGGUGUGAAGAGGCACAAGAAAAUGUAAACCCUAGUUACCACUGAGACGUCCCAUUGUUUAGUCAUUUCAGCACCACUGCAUAGACUUCCGUAAUAUGAGAAAGAGACUUAAUAUCCUAGUCAUGAGGAGCACAGGGUUUAGGGAAAAAUACAUACACAGAUAUAUCUAUAUGUUGAUAUACACACACACAUAUACAUGCACACACACUCACACAUACACAAUCAGUGACUUCUUAUGAUGGUUCAACUAAUGAUUUUCAACCUUAUGAUGGUGUGAAGGCAAUACACAUUGUAGAUGUCCACAAAAUAUUUAAAAAGCUUUAUUCUGAGCCAAAUACCAGUGACCUAGGCCUGUGACACAGCCCCAAGAGAUCCGGAGAACAUGUGCCUAAGGGGGUUGAGCAUGAUUUUAUACAUUUUGUAGGGGAGAGAAGUUACAGGCAGAUAUUCAUCAAUUCAAGGUAUACAUUUGUUUCUUCCAGGAAGGUGGCACAACUUGAAGCAGAGGAUUCCCGGUUAUAGACAGAUUCAGAGGUUUUCAAAUUGGCUAUUGGUUGAAGGAGUUAAGUUACCUAAAGACCUGGAAUCAAUAGAAAGGAGUGUCUGGGUUAAGAAAAGGUGUUGUGGAGACCAAGGUCUUAUGCAGAUAAAGUCUCAUAGUUGGCCAUCCUUAGAAGCAAUAGAUGACAAAAGUUUCCCAUUCAGACCCUUGAAAGAUGCUAGAUGCUCAUCUAAUCACAUCAAGAUGAGCAAAAGACCAGUCAAGGGAAGUAAACCUGAAAAACUUGUUCACACCACUUUAUCCCUCCUUGGAUUAGAUAGUGUUUGCCUCAUGGUUAGAAGAUCUCCUGAUGAAUCUUGAGCAAACAAUGCCCUAAAUGUCUUGAGUUUGAUUAAUUAUCCCAGGUCUCUUUCUUCUGACAAUUCAGGUAAAGAGUAGAAUGCAGCUCUUCCUUAUAAAAGGCAGCUUUGUGAGGCCAUUUCAAAAUAUAUGAAAGAAGUAUAUUUUGGGGUAAAAUGCUUUGAUUUCUUUUAGGGCCUGGUAUCUAUCAUGUGAUGUUACACCAGAGAGGUUGAAAUUUGGUAUCUUUUUGUUAUCAAGUGUCUGUUUGGUUGGUCUUAUGAUUUCUGUUUUAAUGUUAAUUCUGGUCAGUUGUGCCCGAGUUCCAAAGAGAGAAGUGUAUAGUGAGGCAUGUCCAAUCCCCAUAUCCCCUCAUCGCCAGAAGAAGUUUUUCAGGAUUAGUUUGGAAUGCCCUUGGCAGAGAGGGUUUAUAUUCAGUUAACUGGGGACUUAGAAUUUUAAUUUUGGUUUACAGAAUUCACUAGAGACUCUACAUCCAGUACCCAUAUAAUCAUUCUAAUUUGCACUUUUGGUACAGGAUUCAAUAAAUUACAUGAGAUGCUCAACACUUUAUUAUAAAAUAGACUUUCUGUUAGAUGCUUUUACCCAACUGUAGGCUAAAGUAAGUGUACUGCACAUAUUUGAAAUAGACUAGGCUAUGUUGCAUGAUAUAUUUGGUCUAUGUGAUAAAUUUUUGUCUUAUGAUAUUUUGAACAUAUCAUGGGUUUUUCAGAUGUAAUCGCCAUUGCAGUUCCAGGAACAUCUGUAUGUAUUUUAUGUGUGUGUGUGUAUGUCUGUGUGUGUUUGUGUGUGUGUAUGUGUGUUCUUCAACUCCUUGGACAGAUCUCAACCUUUCAGAGGCUUCGUUUUCUUCUUUGUAAAAUGGGAACAGUGGUAUUUCUCUUAUGGAAUGUCAUUGUGGAGUAAUUUAGAAAAGCGUAGCAUUCAACCGGAAACCUUCAUAGCAUUUAUUGCCUGGAAAAUGAUGUUGAUUUCUAGGGGAGAUAAGUACUUUCUUAUUUAUCACAUUUCAUAAAAGGAAGGAACCUACUUUUCUUGAAUUCUAAAACACAUAUGUGCAUUGGGAAUGGGAAUGAGAAUACACUUAGCAAAAUGAUCCCUCUGAAGACAAUGGCAAUGUGUUUGCCAAGGGGAUUAAUUAGACGUAUUUUGCAAUACUGUUUAUAGAAUGGAAAACAAGAAAUUGAGAGGAGGUAGUUGGAAGUGUGCACUUCUCUGCAGAUCAGCCAACUGGCCUCAGUACUUUAGGUAAGGGAUUUUAAUUUGUCCUUUGGUUUACAGGACAACGCAGACUUACUGCUGUUUAUAUUCAUCAAACACACAUACCUGAGUAGCAGAUCUCUACUCUCCCUUUAAAUAAGGUUGCAUUGGAGUUUUCGAAAGACUUAUCUUUCUGCAGGCUCGCCUCUGAGCUUUGUCUCCUUGGAGCCACCUCACUUAGACAGCUUCGGAUGUGGAUGCAGAUUUGAACCAUGUUGCGUCCCCAGGGACUGCUAUGGCUCCCUUUGUUGUUCACCUCUGUCUGUGUCAUGUUAAACUCCAAUGUUCUUCUGUGGAUAACUGCUCUUGCCAUCAAGUUCACCCUCAUUGACAGCCAAGCACAGUAUCCAGUUGUCAACACAAAUUAUGGUAAAAUCCAGGGCCUAAGAACACCAUUACCCAGUGAGAUCUUGGGUCCAGUGGAGCAGUACUUAGGGGUCCCCUAUGCCUCACCCCCAACUGGAGAGAGGCGGUUUCAGCCACCAGAAUCCCCAUCCUCCUGGACUGGCAUCCGAAAUGCUACUCAGUUUUCUGCUGUGUGCCCCCAGCACCUGGAUGAAAGAUUCUUAUUGCAUGACAUGCUGCCCAUCUGGUUUACCACCAGUUUGGAUACUUUGAUGACCUAUGUUCAAGAUCAAAAUGAAGACUGCCUUUACUUAAACAUCUAUGUGCCCAUGGAAGAUGGAACCAACAUAAAGAGAAAUGCAGACGAUAUAACCAGUAAUGACCAUGGUGAAGAUAAAGAUAUUCAUGAACAGAACAGUAAGAAGCCUGUUAUGGUCUAUAUCCAUGGGGGAUCUUACAUGGAGGGAACCGGUAACAUGAUUGAUGGCAGCAUUUUGGCCAGCUAUGGGAACGUCAUCGUUAUCACCAUUAACUACCGUCUGGGAAUACUAGGGUUUUUAAGUACCGGUGACCAGGCAGCAAAAGGCAACUAUGGGCUCCUGGAUCAGAUUCAAGCACUGAGGUGGAUUGAGGAGAAUGUCGGAGCCUUUGGCGGGGACCCCAAGAGAGUGACUAUCUUUGGCUCGGGGGCUGGGGCCUCCUGUGUCAGCCUGUUGACCCUGUCCCACUACUCAGAAGGUCUCUUCCAGAAGGCCAUCAUUCAGAGCGGCACUGCCCUGUCCAGCUGGGCAGUGAACUACCAGCCGGCCAAGUACACUCGGAUAUUGGCAGACAAGGUCGGCUGCAACAUGCUGGACACCACGGACAUGGUAGAAUGUCUGAAGAACAAGAACUACAAGGAGCUCAUCCAGCAGACCAUCACCCCGGCCACCUACCACAUAGCCUUUGGGCCGGUGAUCGACGGCGACGUCAUCCCAGACGACCCCCAGAUCCUGAUGGAGCAAGGCGAGUUCCUCAACUACGACAUCAUGCUGGGCGUCAACCAAGGGGAAGGCCUGAAGUUCGUGGACGGCAUCGUGGAUAACGAGGACGGUGUGACGCCCAACGACUUUGACUUCUCCGUGUCCAACUUCGUGGACAACCUUUACGGCUACCCUGAAGGGAAAGACACUUUGCGGGAGACUAUCAAGUUCAUGUACACAGACUGGGCCGAUAAGGAAAACCCGGAGACGCGGCGGAAAACCCUGGUGGCUCUCUUUACUGACCAUCAGUGGGUGGCCCCCGCCGUGGCCACCGCCGACCUGCACGCGCAGUACGGCUCCCCCACCUACUUCUAUGCCUUCUAUCAUCACUGCCAAAGCGAAAUGAAGCCCAGCUGGGCAGAUUCGGCCCAUGGCGAUGAAGUCCCCUAUGUCUUCGGCAUCCCCAUGAUCGGUCCCACAGAGCUCUUCAGUUGUAAUUUCUCCAAGAACGACGUCAUGCUCAGUGCCGUGGUGAUGACCUACUGGACGAACUUCGCCAAAACUGGUGAUCCAAACCAACCAGUUCCUCAGGAUACCAAGUUCAUUCAUACAAAACCCAAUCGCUUUGAAGAAGUGGCCUGGUCCAAGUAUAAUCCCAAAGACCAGCUCUAUCUGCAUAUUGGCUUGAAACCCAGAGUGAGAGAUCACUACCGGGCAACGAAAGUGGCUUUCUGGUUGGAAUUGGUUCCUCAUUUGCACAACUUGAACGAGAUAUUCCAGUAUGUUUCAACAACCACAAAGGUUCCUCCACCAGACAUGACAUCAUUUCCCUAUGGCACCCGGCGAUCUCCCGCCAAGAUAUGGCCAACCACCAAACGCCCAGCAAUCACUCCUGCCAACAAUCCCAAACACUCUAAGGACCCUCACAAAACAGGGCCCGAGGACACAACUGUCCUCAUUGAAACCAAACGAGAUUAUUCCACCGAAUUAAGUGUCACCAUUGCCGUCGGGGCGUCGCUCCUCUUCCUCAACAUCUUAGCCUUUGCGGCGCUGUACUACAAAAAGGACAAGAGGCGCCAUGAGACUCACAGGCACCCCAGUCCCCAGAGAAACACCACAAAUGAUAUCACUCACAUCCAGAACGAAGAGAUCAUGUCUCUGCAGAUGAAGCAGCUGGAACACGAUCACGAGUGUGAGUCGCUGCAGGCACACGACACGCUGAGGCUCACCUGCCCUCCAGACUACACCCUCACGCUGCGCCGGUCGCCGGAUGACAUCCCAUUUAUGACGCCAAACACCAUCACCAUGAUUCCAAACACAUUGAUGGGGAUGCAGCCUUUACACACUUUUAAAACCUUCAGUGGAGGACAAAACAGUACAAAUUUACCCCACGGACAUUCCACCACUAGAGUAUAGCUUUUCCCUAUUUCCCCUCCUAUCCCUCUGCCCCUACUGCUCAGCAAUGUAAAAGAGACAAAUAAGGAGAAAGAAAAUCUCCAAACCAGGAAUGUUUUUGUGCCACUGACUUUAGAUAAAAAUGCAAAAGGGCAGUCAUCCUGUCCCAGCAGACCCUUCUCAUUGGCAUUUUCCAGUAUUGUGAGAUCAAUUUCUGACCAUAUGAAAUGUGAAAAGUAUAUGUUUCUGUUACAAUACUGCUUUAAGAUCUAAACCAUGCCAACAGAUGUUUCGUGUGACUAGGACAUCACCAUUUCAAGGAACUGUGUGUUUCCAACAUCAUGGUAGCAGCACACACUUCCAAAGCUCAGCCAGGGACACUUAAUAUUUUUUAAUUACAAUGGAAAUUUAAACAUUUUUAUGUGGGCUACACAAUGGAUGGCUCUUCUUAAGUGAAGAAAGACUCUAUAGGCUUUUACACAGCACAUGAAGCAGUAAUCCAGAAAGAAGGAAAUGCAGAAUUUUAUUAUCAAAGUAAGCGAAUUGACUGUGCAGAAAAAUUGUAGGGUUCUGUGGAAGGAGGUAUUCUGCCAGCCUGAACUAUAUUUAAGAAACUUUGUAAAAAAUAAAAAUGUAUAUAGCUGUGAGCUCAAACAAAAACUGCAGACAAACAAAAAAGAGAAAAGCUUUUAUUUGUGUUUUCAGUUUGAAAGAACUUUUAGCAAGGUUGUGCUUUCAAACACAUAUUAGUCCUACCACCUUAGUUCCUCUACAGCAAAAGAGGCUUUUCUUCUUAAUUACAUGUAAACAAAGACAUGGGAUUUUCUGACGUAAGAUUUUCAUUUGUAGGAAUAUGUGAUGUCAAAUGGAAGACUCAGAAGUUUUGUGUGGCCUAUUUCUCCCUGUCAGGUUGCACAGAUGCAUGUAGAGCAUUCUUAGGAGACCAUUGUUUUAGAAAACUUUGAUUUGUACAUGUUAGUUUUCAUGAAAUUGCAACACAGAGAUAGGUCCUAAAAGUGGAAUGUAUUUAAAACUUGUUGAAUUAGACACACACACACAGACACACACAAAGAAUCAGCAGAGAAAACAAAAUACAAGUCCUGUUCUGUAGUUCUUGCCCUUUGAAUAUAUUUGGGAAGAGUUGCUUCCUAUUUCAGGACCCUGCCAAAAAAGAAGAAAGCUUGCCUUUGGUGGGGCUAUGCCCCUUGGAGUAAAUACAGCUCUGUGUUCCCUAGCAGCUGCCGGAGGAUUUGGCUGAUGAAGUACCUGCUCAGCUUAGCUAAUCAGAUUAAAGGAAGACAUGUAUGUCUUUUGUUUAAGCACCUAGUCCCUUAUGUAUCAGUAAACAGGUUUUUAAAAAUCUUUUAUGUCAUUUAUAGGAUAAAACAUAUGCUUGUCUGAAAAUAUCACCUUUUGUGGAUUUAUCUGAUCACCAAAUAAUAAAUAUUAAGAAGAAUGGGGGAAAAAGGAUAGAAUAUUAAAACUGCUUUGCAUAGGUUUUUGGGGAAAUUAGGAUAUCUUCACUGACAAGACACUGAAUGGAAUUUAUUCACCCAUUUUAAAUUGGUUACUUGGGGAUCAGAGAUUUGUCUCUCCAACAGCUUGUGGUUUUCUUAUUACUCAUUUUCAGGAAAGUUUGUAGUAUUACAAGGCAGAAGGAAACACAGUAGCAAUGGUUGCUCUAUAUUUUGUCUUUCAAAGAUUACUGCAUUACCAAGAAACAGUAGCCAAAGAUGUUUGAAGAUCAUGUCCCUUAGCUGCAUUGUGGGUUAUUCUAGAAAUCCAAUGUUAAAUGCCUCUACUAAAGUGGGGAUUCCCCAUAAAAAUUGUCCAGCUACCUGACUCUUUUGCAAUAACAACUUUGAUUACUGAAUCCAUACACUCAAACUAUAGUGAUAUAUCAGUGUUUGGGAGUGACCUCUAGAAAAAAGAAAACUGUUUUUAGAAAUACAUAAAAUCACUUCCAAAUCCUGUUGCUUAUGUUGGGUUAAAUUUGAAAGCAAUUCUCUAUAUAUAAAUAUGUGAAAUAUUAUGAUCUGAACUUAGCACACAUGAAGCAACAUUUCUUUGCUACACAGAGGUGUCUUGGAAAGAUUUCAUUCCCAAUUCAUUUUUCAUAGAUCUAUAAUCAGGCAAUUUCUGCAAGCAAUGUAUGACCCCACCUGAGCAACCACAAAUAGGCUCUCCAUGAAACUGCAAAGGAACUGAUGUGUGGCAUCCAUGCUGGUUUUGUCUGUCUAUAAUAUGAAUUCAAGUAUCUGUUCAUAUUUCCAAUUGUCUCCUGCUAGCAAUAUGUGCCACAACAUGACAGUCUUGUGACAUCUUAAGGAAAAGAAGAGUUCCUGUUAAAUGAAUAGCUUUAGCUUUUACAGGGGAUUAUGAUUAAAAGUGAUUUAGUACAUCUUACAUGAUAUCUCAUUUCUACGUGAAAAGAAGUUAUAGAAUCUUCAUAGAGUUCCAUGAGAAAAAUAUACUUGCUAUUUAUAGAAAACGAGAAAAAAGAAAAAAAUGAGAAACAAGUAAGAAAAAAUCCUUUCCUAGGCUUUUCCUUGAUCUUCAGAGGCACACAGGGUUUAAUGGUUCCUUAGGUUAUUAUUUUGAGGUUUUGUUCUUUCUUUUGCCUUAAGUAAUGACAGAAGAUAUAUAUGGCCAGACACAUAUGUAUAAACUUUUCAGCAGCAUUUUAAUAAUAAAAUAUCACACUAUUUUCUAAUGCUUUGUACAAACAAUUAUGCAUCUGUUCUUUCUUGGUAGGUGGAAUAUUUUAUUUACUUUUGCCAUUCUUUGAAUGCCUUUUUCUUUGUAAAUGCUACAUGGUAGCUCUCACAUAGGCUACAAAUGGAUAAAUACAUUUGGUAAUGGGAUGGUUUCUUUAGCUUUGGCCAGCUGCACAGUUGAGGAGGCUCUGCUGGCCUGAUUUUGGAAAACCAAGCCCUGUUUGGUGAAGCUCCUGAGAUGACACUGCCUGAAAAUGAGUAUUUGGUUGUGUUAUUUCUACCACUGUUCAUUCUUGUGUCUCUGUGUUUUGAUUUGUGUUCAACAAACUGAUGCCUUAAUGGUUUCAAAUAGAAAGCCUUAGGUGAGUAAACCUUCUAGUGACAGUAAGAAAUUCUACUGAAUGAAACUCCAGAGGCAGAAAAUCAUUGUCAUUCCAAUGGGAGCUCAAUUGUCAAUUCCUUCCUGUGCAUUCAGCCAUCACGAACUUAUUUCACAUUCACAGUAGCUCUAAGGGGCAGGCACCUGCAUUACUCCCCUUUCAUAAUGGAAGAUGUUCUGACUUUGAAACAUGCCCCCUUGGACAGGAAAAUUUGAUGGAUAACAGGAUAGCAUAUCCUCAUAUCCCAAUCUUUCACCAAGAAGUUAUACAGCAAACACUUGUAAGUCAAGGUCUUGCAUGAUAAUCUUUGCUAAGUAGCAAGUAAAGAAAUAUAGCAAGGACCCAGACUCUUUGGAAUAUGUGAACUAAAUCCUUCAGAUGUUGUUGGCCUCAAUCAUGUUGUGAAGGCACACAGGAGAAUACAUACACACACAUAUGCAUAUAUGUAUAUAUGUACAUGUAUGUGUACAUUAUAUAUGAGUAUACAUGUACCUAUCCUAUAUAUGUAUGUAUGUAUAGAGUCACAGACUGCAUAAUGUUUUGGACAAAUAUAGAUCACAUAUAUGAUGAUAGUGUCUUGAGAUUAAAAUACCAUGUUUUUAUUGUACCUUUUCAGUGUUCAGAUAUGUUUAGACAAACAAAUGCUUAUCAUUGUGUUACAGUUGCCUAAGGUCUUCUCUCCAGUCACAUGCUGUACAGGUUUGUAGACUGGAAGAACUAGGCUAUACCAUAGAGCCUAGGUGUGCUAUAGGCUACACAUCGGUUUUGUGUAAGUAUACUACAUGAUGUUUGCACAAUGAUGAAAUUGCCUAACGAAACUUUUCUCAGAAACCUAUUGAUACAUGACUGUGUAUGUUUACAUUAUAUAUACUGUAUAUGCACACAUGCAUAUAUGCAUAUAUAUGUUAUACAUUUACAUAUGUACAUGGAUAUCACAUACUUUAAAUUCCUGAAGAUGUCAUUUUCAUUAAAUACAUAUGCACACACACUCAUAAACACACACAGACUCAUAUAUACACACAAAUCUAUAACACAUUUGUGCUCACAUAUACAUUCCUCUGUGUGUGUGUGUGUAUUACAUUACUGCUUUUUAUCUGUGAAAUCACAUUCUGCAGUUUCAUUUACUGUGAUCAACUAUGAUCUAAAAAUAUAUGAGUACUUCAAUAAGAUAUUUUGAAAGAAACCACAUUCACAUAACAUUUAUGACAUUAUAAUUGUUCUAUUUUAUUAGCUAUUGUUCAUCUCUUACUCCAUCUACUUUAUAAAUUAAGCUUCAUAAUAAGUGUGUAUAUUUAAUAAAAUAUAUAGUAUAUAAA